ACACCCGGAAGCAGGGGCCCGAGCGGAGCCGGCCGCGAUGAGCGGGGAGCCGGGGCAGACGUCCGUAGCGCCCCCUCCCGAGGAGGUCGAGCCGGGCAGUGGGGUCCGCAUCGUGGUGGAGUACUGUGAACCCUGCGGCUUCGAGGCGACCUACCUGGAGCUGGCCAGUGCUGUGAAGGAGCAGUAUCCGGGCAUCGAGAUCGAGUCGCGCCUCGGGGGCACAGGUGCCUUUGAGAUAGAGAUAAAUGGACAGCUGGUGUUCUCCAAGCUGGAGAAUGGGGGCUUUCCCUAUGAGAAAGAUGUGAGUAUUUACAGCGUUGGGAGGACCUCUUGGUCACCCUACCCCAACAGUGCAUCAUCCUGUCAUUCCACUCCUCUAGCUCAUUGAGGCCAUCCGAAGAGCCAGUAAUGGAGAAACCCUAGAAAAGAUCACCAACAGCCGUCCUCCCUGCGUCAUCCUGUGACUGCACAGGACUCUGGGUUCCUGCUCUGUUCUGGGGUCCAAACCUUGGUCUCCCUUUGGUCCUGCUGGGAGCUCCCCCUGCCUCUUUCCCCUACUUAGCUCCUUAGCAAAGAGACCCUGGCCUCCACUUUGCCCUUUGGGUACAAAGAAGGAAUAGAAGAUUCCGUGGCCUUGGGGGCAGGAGAGAGACACUCUCCAUGAACACUUCUCCAGCCACCUCAUACCCCCUUCCCAGGGUAAGUGCCCACGAAAGCCCAGUCCACUCUUCGCCUCGGUAAUACCUGUCUGAUGCCACAGAUUUUAUUUAUUCUCCCCUAACCCAGGGCAAUGUCAGCUAUUGGCAGUAAAGUGGCGCUACAAACACUAAUGCUAACUAGUGUGUGUUUUUAUACGUCCAGUCUGGGAAUGUGGGGGGCACAGAAGUCCGGUCAGCCCAGCCUUUGCACCGCCAGGGUGGCUGUGCUGGCUGGGUGGGCUUUCUGGACAGCUACUCCUUAGGUCAGUGAGCUCCUCUGGCAUAGCCAAGGCAAGGAAAAUGAGUCCCACAGUAGACCCUGCCUCGUCUUUCCCCCACCCUACCCACCACUCUCCUCACUCACAAGGAGGAAAUAACCCCAUUCUGGUGAGUGGCCUUAGGAAUUAGUUCGUUCUAAAUAAGAAUGAUCUGGUCGUCAAAGGGCUCUCAGAUCUGAAUCCAGCUUCCCGAUCUCCCCCAACCCUGAAGCUGGAGAACUGGAUGUCUGGCUCCUCAUCCAAGCUUUCUGAAGAUUCCCAGCCACUCCCUCCAGGAAAAGAGGAAUUGAGUGUAAGGUGAGCAGGAAGGGAUGGCACAGAGCCACCCCCAGACAUAGGCCGGUGCCUAGCUGUUUUCCAAAAUAUAUUUGCAAAUGGACAAAGUGGGUGUGGAGAAGGACCCCCCACACUUGCCUCCCCAUACAACACCCAUUCUCCCCCUGGGUCUUUAUUUCAUCUUUAAAAAAACAAAACAAAAAAAGUAAAAACUAAACAGAAAA